GAGGGUGCUUUAUUGGGUGGAGGGCACCAUGUCCCAGGGCUAUCAAAUAAAGAAUAGUUUGGUUUUUUUUUUAAAUAAAGGUUUUAUUAGCAUUUGCCCAAGAAGGCAGAUACUUUCAUAUCUGUAAAAGUGGGAGCUGUGAUCUGUACCCUCUGCCAAACGUUUACGUGGGAGGCGGGAGCGGGGGCUGAGGGCUUCGUCUUUUCUCCCCUCUGCUAUCACCGGUUCUGGACCUUGGCCUGGAUCAUCUUCCCCUCUGCUAAUACCCCCUACCCCGUCCGUCACAUCAGGGAGGUGUGCCCUCUAGCUAUCCACGCCCCCUCCUUGGUCACUAGUUAUAGGUAACUUUCACCCUUCCGCCGGCCACCCCAGCCCCAGGGAAGAACGUUCCUUUGGUGGGUGUCGGCAAAUGGGGACCGGACCCCAGAGUCCAGAGGCGGGGCUAGCGCGCGCUCCCAAACUGUUGGCUCUUUCCUCCCGUCCCGCCCUUUCCCUGCCUUUCCGUUCGAACGGCUGGGGCUCUGCCCGCUCGCUGCCCAUUGGCUGGCUCUCGGUGGCGUCACCGCCUUGGGUCCUCGCGCCCUUCGUCUGCGCCAGCCCUGGAAGCACGGGGCGGGACGUCCACGGGAAGCGGCGCGCACGCCCGCCGACUCCCUCGCGCCAACCGCCGACGGCCGCCGCCCGGUGAAGGAGGGGCUCAGUCCUCCCAGGCCCCCCCAGGAUGCAAUGGCGCAGCCCCCCCGGCUGAGCCGCUCUGGUGCCUCCUCACUUUGGGACCCAGCUUCUCCUGCUCCCACCUCUGGCCCCAGGCCUCGGCUUUGGGAGGGUCAAGAUGUGCUGGCCAGAUGGACUGAUGGGCUGCUAUACUUGGGUACCAUCAAAAAGGUGGACAGUGCUAGGGAGGUGUGUCUGGUCCAGUUUGAGGAUGAUUCGCAGUUUCUGGUUCUAUGGAAAGACAUUAGCCCUGCUGCCCUCCCUGGAGAGGAACUCCUCUGUUGUGUCUGUCGCUCUGAGACUGUGGUCCCUGGGAACCGGCUGGUCAGCUGUGAGAAGUGUCGCCAUGCUUAUCACCAGGACUGCCAUGUUCCCAGGGCUCCAGCCCCUGGAGAGGGAGAGGGCACAUCCUGGGUAUGCCGCCAGUGUGUCUUUGCGAUCGCCACCAAGAGGGGAGGUGCCCUGAAGAAGGGCCCCUAUGCCCGGGCCAUGCUGGGUAUGAAGCUUUCUCUGCCAUAUGGACUGAAGGGGCUGGACUGGGAUGCUGGACAUCUGAGCAACCGACAGCAGAGUUACUGUUACUGUGGUGGCCCUGGGGAGUGGAACCUGAAAAUGCUGCAGUGCCGGAGCUGCCUGCAGUGGUUCCAUGAGGCCUGCACCCAGUGUCUGAGCAAGCCCCUCCUCUAUGGGGACAGGUUCUAUGAAUUUGAAUGCUGUGUGUGUCGCGGGGGCCCUGAGAAAGUCCGGAGACUACAGCUUCGCUGGGUGGAUGUGGCCCAUCUUGUCCUGUAUCACCUCAGUGUUUGCUGUAAGAAGAAAUACUUUGAUUUUGAUCGUGAGAUCCUCCCCUUCACUUCUGAGAAUUGGGACAGUUUGCUCCUGGGGGAGCUUUCAGACACCCCCAAAGGAGAACGUUCUUCCAAGCUCCUCUCUGCUCUUAACAGCCACAAGGACCGUUUCAUUUCAGGGAGAGAGAUUAAGAAGAGGAAAUGUUUGUUUGGUCUCCAUGCUCGGAUGCCUCCCCCUGUGGAGCCCCCUACUGGAGAUGGAGCACUCACCAGCUUCCCUUCAGGGCAGGGCCCUGGGGGAGGGGUCUCACGUCCCCUGGGGAAGCGCCGGAGGCCGGAGCCAGAGCCCCUGAGGAGGAGGCAGAAGGGGAAAGUGGAGGAGCUGGGGCCACCCUCAGCAGUGCGCAAUCAGCCCGAGCCCCAGGAGCAGAGGGAGCGGGCUCAUCUGCAGAGGGCACUGCAGGCCUCAGUGUCUCCACCAUCCCCCAGCCCUAACCAGAGUUACCAGGGCAGCAGCGGCUACAACUUCCGGCCCACAGAUGCCCGCUGCCUGCCCAGCAGCCCCAUCCGGAUGUUUGCUUCCUUCCACCCUUCUGCCAGCACCGCAGGGACCUCUGGGGACAGUGGACCCCCAGACAGGUCACCCCUGGAACUUCACAUUGGUUUCCCCACAGACAUCCCUAAAAGUGCCCCCCACUCGAUGACUGCCUCAUCUUCCUCAGUUUCAUCCCCAUCCCCAGGUCUUCCUAGACGCUCAGCACCCCCUUCUCCCCUGUGCCGUAGUUUGUCUCCUGGGACUGGGGGAGGAGUCCGAGGUGGGGUUGGUUACCUGUCCCGAGGGGACCCUGUCCGGGUCCUUGCUCGGAGAGUACGGCCUGAUGGCUCUGUGCAGUACCUGGUUGAGUGGGGAGGAGGGGGCAUCUUCUGAACAGCCUGCCUCUGCCCAGCUCCCCAUUCACACACACCGGCACUUUCAUACCCUGACCUCUGACCUCACCUACAGCUGGGAUGUACCUGGAGAGAUAGGGGGUAGUUCUCCCUACUGCCCAGGCUGGAAUCCAAGAGUGGGGAGUGGGGAAGAGGCCCUCUUCUCUACCCUCCUUCAUGAUUCCUGACCCCUCCCAUCCUUCCCAUUUCCUUUGAUGUUAUUUUGUUACAGCUUUUUAAAUAUUUUUUAAAAUUAUUUAACCCCUGGGGGCAGAGACUGAGGAGGGAGGAUGAUAAGGGAUCCCGGACUCUGUAUGAUUGAAAUAAAGAGAAAUAAACAAA